AGCUCGCGCUGCCCGGGCGGGCGCCGGCCGCUGGCGCCGCUACUGCUGCCGCCCCCGGGGCGCGAGUCCGCCGCCCGCCGCCCGGGCACCCGGCGAGGGGCGGGGGCAGCUCCGAACCGGCCCCAGAUCCUUCCCGCUUCCGCCUCACGCUUCCCGGAAAGCUUGUCCCUCUCCGCCGAGCUGCUCCGGGAGCCCCGCCGCGCCGAGGGAGGCCCCAGGGACCCUCUACCCUCAAACACAGGGUAUCUCCCAGAGCCCCAGCUGGUGUGGCCAGGCCCCAGGAGUAGGAUGGGGCUCCCCCUACGAGGGCCGGUGGCAGCCAGAACUGAUACAGCCCCCCUGGUCUGGGGCCAGGACGCCAGCUGAGGAGGGCAGGAGUGUCUGGAGCUAUGGCUGGUGCCUCGGUGAAAGUGGCAGUGAGGGUUCGGCCCUUUAACGCCCGUGAGACCAGCCAGGAUGCCAAGUGUGUGGUCAGCAUGCAGGGCAACACCACCUCCAUCAUCAAUCCUAAACAGAGCAAGGAUGCCCCCAAAAGCUUCACCUUUGACUACUCCUACUGGUCACACACUUCGACGGAGGACCCCCAGUUUGCAUCUCAGCAGCAAGUGUAUCGGGACAUUGGAGAAGAGAUGCUGCUCCACGCCUUUGAAGGCUACAACGUGUGCAUCUUUGCCUAUGGGCAGACCGGGGCUGGGAAAUCCUAUACCAUGAUGGGGCGACAGGAGCCAGGGCAGCAGGGCAUCGUGCCCCAGCUCUGUGAGGACCUCUUCUCUCGCGUUAGUGAGAACCAGAGUGCUCAGCUAUCCUACUCUGUGGAGGUGAGCUAUAUGGAGAUCUACUGUGAGCGGGUACGAGACCUCUUGAACCCCAAGAGUCGGGGUUCUCUGCGGGUCCGGGAGCACCCCAUCCUGGGCCCGUACGUGCAGGACCUGUCCAAAUUGGCUGUGACCUCCUACGCAGACAUUGCUGACCUCAUGGACUGUGGAAAUAAAGCACGGACUGUGGCUGCCACCAACAUGAAUGAGACCAGCAGCCGUUCCCAUGCCGUCUUUACCAUCGUCUUCACACAGCGCUGCCAUGACCAGCUCACGGGGCUGGACUCGGAGAAGGUCAGUAAGAUCAGUUUGGUGGACCUUGCUGGGAGUGAGCGAGCCGACUCCUCAGGGGCCCGGGGCAUGCGCCUGAAGGAAGGAGCCAACAUCAAUAAGUCCCUGACUACACUAGGGAAAGUGAUCUCGGCCCUUGCAGAUAUGCAAUCAAAGAAGCGAAAGUCGGAUUUUAUCCCCUACAGGGACUCUGUGCUCACCUGGCUGCUCAAGGAAAAUUUGGGGGGGAACUCACGCACAGCCAUGAUUGCAGCCCUGAGCCCUGCUGACAUCAAUUACGAGGAGACUCUCAGCACCCUCAGGUAUGCUGACCGCACCAAGCAAAUCCGCUGCAAUGCCAUCAUCAACGAGGACCCUAAUGCCCGGCUGAUUAGAGAGCUGCAGGAGGAAGUAGCCCGGCUGCGGGAACUGCUGAUGGCUCAGGGACUGUCAGCCUCUGCUCUGGAAGGCCUGAAGACGGAAGAAGGGAGUGUCAGAGGCGCCCUGCCAGCUGUGUCAUCUCCCCCAGCUCCAGUUUCACCCUCAUCACCCACCACACAUAAUGGGGAGCUGGAGCCGUCAUUCUCCCCCAACACGGAGUCCCAGAUUGGGCCUGAGGAAGCCAUGGAGAGGCUGCAGGAGACAGAGAAGAUUAUAGCUGAGCUGAACGAGACAUGGGAGGAGAAGCUACGCAAGACAGAAGCCCUGAGGAUGGAGAGAGAAGCAUUGCUGGCUGAGAUGGGGGUGGCCGUCCGGGAGGAUGGGGGAACUGUGGGCGUCUUCUCUCCAAAGAAGACUCCCCACCUGGUGAACCUGAACGAAGACCCUCUGAUGUCUGAGUGUCUGCUCUACCACAUCAAAGAUGGCGUCACCAGGGUCGGCCAAGUAGAUAUGGACAUCAAGCUGACCGGACAGUUCAUUCGGGAGCAACACUGUCUGUUCCGGAGCAUCCCCCAGCCAGAUGGAGAAGUGGUGGUCACUCUGGAGCCUUGUGAAGGAGCUGAGACAUAUGUGAAUGGGAAGCUUGUGACGGAGCCGCUGGUGCUGAAGUCAGGGAAUAGGAUUGUGAUGGGCAAGAACCACGUUUUCCGCUUCAACCACCCGGAGCAGGCAAGGCUGGAACGGGAACGAGGGGUCCCCCCACCCCCAGGACCGCCCUCUGAGCCAGUCGACUGGAACUUUGCCCAGAAGGAACUGCUGGAGCAGCAAGGCAUCGACAUAAAGCUGGAAAUGGAGAAGAGGCUGCAGGAUCUGGAGAAUCAGUACCGGAAAGAAAAGGAAGAAGCCGAUCUUCUGCUGGAGCAGCAGCGACUGUAUGCAGACUCGGACAGCGGGGAUGACUCUGACAAGCGCUCUUGUGAAGAGAGCUGGAGGCUCAUCUCCUCCUUGCGGGAGCAGCUGCCGCCCACCACGGUCCAGACCAUUGUCAAACGCUGUGGUCUGCCCAGCAGUGGCAAGCGCAGGGCCCCUCGCAGGGUUUAUCAGAUCCCCCAGCGACGCAGGCUGCAGGGCAAAGACCCCCGCUGGGCCACCAUGGCUGACCUGAAGAUGCAGGCGGUGAAGGAGAUCUGCUACGAGGUGGCCCUGGCUGACUUCCGCCACGGGCGGGCUGAGAUUGAGGCCCUGGCCGCCCUCAAGAUGCGGGAGCUGUGUCGCACCUAUGGCAAGCCAGACGGCCCCGGAGACGCCUGGAGGGCUGUGGCCCGGGAUGUCUGGGACACUGUAGGCGAGGAGGAAGGAGGUGGAGCUGGCAGUGGUGGUGGCAGUGAGGAGGGAGCCCGAGGGGCGGAGGUGGAGGACCUCCGGGCCCACAUCGACAAGCUGACGGGGAUUCUGCAGGAGGUGAAGCUGCAGAACAGCAGCAAGGACCGGGAGCUGCAGGCCCUGCGGGACCGCAUGCUCCGCAUGGAGAGGGUCAUCCCCCUGGCCCAGGAUCAUGAGGAUGAGAAUGAAGAAGGUGGUGAGGUCCCCUGGGCCCCGCCUGAAGGAUCAGAGGCAGCAGAGGAGGCAGCCCCCAGUGACCGCAUGCCGUCAGCCCGGCCCCCCUCGCCACCACUGUCAAGCUGGGAGCGGGUGUCACGGCUCAUGGAGGAGGACCCUGCCUUCCGUCGUGGUCGUCUUCGCUGGCUCAAGCAGGAGCAGCUACGGCUGCAGGGACUGCAGGGCUCUGGGGGCCGGGGCGGGGGGCUGCGCAGGCCCCCAGCCCGCUUUGUGCCCCCUCACGACUGCAAGCUACGCUUCCCCUUCAAGAGCAACCCCCAGCACCGGGAGUCUUGGCCAGGGAUGGGGAGCGGGGAGGCUCCAACUCCGCUCCAACCCCCUGAGGAGGUCACUCCCCAUCCAGCCACCCCUGCCCGCCGGCCUCCGAGUCCCCGAAGGUCCCACCAUCCCCGCAGGAACUCCCUGGAUGGAGGGGGCCGAUCCCGGGGAGCGGGUUCUGCACAGCCUGAACCCCAGCACUUCCAGCCCAAAAAGCACAACUCUUAUCCCCAGCCACCCCAACCCUACCCAGCCCAGCGGCCCCCAGGGCCCCGCUACCCCCCAUACACUACUCCCCCACGAAUGAGACGGCAGCGUUCUGCCCCUGACCUCAAGGAGAGUGGGGCAGCUGUGUGAGUCCCACAUCCUGGGCAGAGGGCCUGGUGGGGCCCCUUGCUAGGAGAAGGGAAGACGCCCGAGACGCUGCUUCCCCAGAAGUGCUGGGGCAGGGAGGCCCAGGAGAUGAGAGAGAAGGUCCGAGUAGGUGAUAGAAGACAAGGGGGAGACCGAGCCGGAGGCUGAGGAAAGGAAGAGGGCACGGAGUUGCCAGGAGCAAACCAAAGUGAAGAGAGAGAUAGGAAGCUGCCUCGGGGCCACCCCUUGCAAAGGGGGUGUGUCCCACAAACGCUGCUAUGGGUGGGGUGGGGGGCUGGGGUGCUGCGUAGCCAGUGUUUGACUUUCUUUUCAAGUGGGGGAAAGUGGGAGAGGACUGAGAGUGAGGCAAGUUCUCCCCAGCCCCUGUCCGUCUGUCUGUCUGUCUGUGGUGGUUUCUGUUUCUUGGGAGGCAUGGUAGGAUCAUAAGUCAUUCCCCUCCCCUUCCAGGCCUCCUGCUAUAUUUGGGGGACCUGACUGGUUUGGCUGGAGUCCCAUGAGGAUGUGGGCCCUUUAAUAAAGGAUAGCAAACAGGGAGCUUGUGGCCUGUUUGUUUUGGGUUUUCAUGGAGGUGUAGGUUAUAUAAGGCAAUGGCACAGGUCUUAAGCAUACUUAUCAGUGAAGUAUUGUAUGUGUGCUCUGUGCAGGCACCACCCAGAUCUGGAUAUAAGAAUGUUUCCAUCUUGUCUUCCUGAACUUCACCCUCCUGUCUCUUCCUUCAGGGUGCGCAGCCCGAUCUUUUCCCCGCUUUUUUUUUUUGGGAGACAGGGUCUUGCUUUGUUGCCCAGGCUGGAGGUACAGUCUUGGCUCACUGCAGCCUCCGCCUCCUGAGUAGCUGGGAUUACAGGCAUGUGCCACCACGCCCGGCUCAUUACUGUUUUUUUUGUAGUGACGAGGUUUCACCAUAUUGGCCAGGCUGGUCUCGAACUCCUGAUGACCUCAAGUGAUCCGCCCACCUUGGCCUCCCAAAGUGGUGGGAUUACAGGUGUGAGCCACCGCGCCCGGCCUCCCCUGCUUUCAUGUUUGCUUACCCAGUGUCUCAGUCUGUGCCAGCAGCACCACUGUCUGUUAUGGACAAAGCACAGAAGCGGGGAUGCGAGGGGAGGUAGAGGGACCGCCAGCCUGUCAAUGCUUAACUGGCUGUUGCUGACAGAUACAGAAGGAUUUGUGGGGUACAGAGGAGUUCUGCUUUAAGUCACCUAACUUACUUGAAAGGUCUCCCAAGCAGCCAGUUUCUCUUGAUAGUGAAUGGGUUGGGCAAGCAUACUGCGCUUACCUGAUUGUUUUCAUCCUGGUUGUGUUACCUGCCUUCUGGCAGGCUACAUCAUUGUUCCCAGUCGUUAUUUUAUUUGUGUUAAGACUGUUUGUUGGCCAGGCGCAGUGGUUCACGCCUGUAAUGCCAGCACUGGGAGGCCGAGGCAGGUGGAUCACGAGGUCAGGAGAUCGAGACCAUCCUGGCUAUCAUGGUGAAACCCCAUCUCUACUAAAAAUAAAAAUAAAAAAAUUAGCCGGGCAUGGUGGCGGGGGCCUGUAGUCCCAGCUACUCAGGAGGCUGAGGCAGGAGAAUGGCAUGAACCUGGGAGGCGGAGCUUGCAGUGAGCUGAGAUUGCGCCACUGCACUCCAGCCUGGGCGACAGAGCGAGACUCCAUUUCAAGAAAAAUUAAAAAACUGUUUGUUGCCUGCUUGUUUUAAUGUUCUGGCUUGAGGCAGCGAGCCCUUGACUAUGCCACAUUGCCAGGAUUUUGCAGGUUAGAUUGUACUACAGCACUGCCUUUGGCUUGCCAGACUCUGGAGUCCCCACAUUUUCAUCCUGUUCUCAGGAAAACACUUUGACCCACUUGAAGCUCUGAGCUACUGCUUCACAGCUUCCUGGGGUCAGUCUCCAGCCAAAACCAUAGAUAUCCCAACUGCAGCCAAACCACGGCUCUGGGCGAAGGAACGAUUAGGUUUACUCUAGGUUUCCACACCCUGAUGCUCCUGCCUUUACUUUGACACCUCUGACUGCCAGGUUUUCACAGACCUGUUGACAGUGACUCAAGAUCUGGAAUGUAAUGGAUGGUUUGGCAACAGUGUUUGCUUGAGCAGUUUAAAAUCUGGCCAGGGAGACUCAAUGUGAGCAAGAAAAUGAUAGAAUACCAAGUUUUCUGGAGGUCAGAGGGAGCUGAGUUGAGUGUUACCGAGAAUGCUGUGGGGUUUGAGAUGAGAAAAAUAGCUUGCUAAUUUAAAAGACGGAUUAUUUUUCCCUAAAGACCUUGACUUAUGUAAAUGUAUAUUAUCCAUAAUUUUAAAAAUCCACUUAUGGCUGGGCACAGAAGCUCACACCUGUAAUCCCAGCACUUUGGGAGGCUGAGGCAGGAGGAUCAGUUGAGUCCAGGAGUUCGAGACCAGCCUGGGCAACAUAGUGAAACCCUGUAUCUACAAAACAUAGAAAAACUAGUUGGGUGUGGUGGUGUGUACCUGUAGUUCCAGCUACUAGGGAGGUAGGAAGAUCACCUGAGCCCAUGGAGAUUGAGGCUGUGGUGAGCUGUGAAGGCACCACAGCACUCUGGCCUGGGCAAGAGUGGGACUCUCUCAAAAAAAAAAAAAAAAAAAAAUCCACAUAUCCAGCCUUCCAAGUCAGUCUUUAAUAAUGUGCACGGGCCAGGCACAGUGGCUCACACCCGUAAUCCCAACACUUUGGAAUAUUAGGGUGGGAGCAUCACUUGAGGCCAGGAAUUUGAGACCAGCCUGGGCAACAUAGUGAGACUGCCCCCCCCAUCUCUACAAAAAAUAAAAAUCAAAAAUAAUACUGUGGGCAAACUUUACUUAGAUUUUAUUCAGAGUAGUGCCUGUUUAUUUUUCAUCUGUGCUACCUGUGCCGGCAUUCCAUAUGCAUUUGAUUUAGUCUUUAAAGUACCCCGGUAAAAUAGGUCUUUUGUCUGCAUUUUUCAGAUGGGAAGACUGAGGUUUUGUUUAUUUAUUUUUAUUUAUUUAUUUUUUGAGACGGAGUCUCGCUCUGUUGCCUAGGCUGGAGUGCGAUGGCACAAUCUUGGCUCACUACAACCUCCGCUUCCUGGGUUCAAGCGAUUCUCCUGCCUCAGCCUCCUGAGUAGCUAGGAUUACAGGCGCCCACAACCGCACCCGGCUAAUUUUUUGUAUCUUUAGUAGAGACAGGGUUUCACUAUGUUGUCCAAGCUGGUUUCGAAUUCCUGACCUCAGGUGAUCCACCCGCCUCUGCCUCCCAAAAUGUUGGGAUUACAGGCGUGAGCCACCACGCCCAGCCUAUUUAUUUAUUUUUUUAGAAUCAAGAUCUUGCUAUGUUGCCCAGGCUGAACUCGAACUCCUGGGCUCAAGCAAUCCUGCCUCCCAAGCCAAGCAGCUGGUACUGCAAGCAUGUGCCACCGUGCCUGGCUCCUGAAGACUGAGGUUGGUUUAGAUUAAUGAGUUGCCCAAAUUCAGACAGUUCUUAAGUGGCAAAGUUAGGAUUCCAACCCAGGUCAACAUAACUAAAGCCCAAACCCCAUCUCACCCCUCUAGGCCAUCAAGUAUUGGCUGGGUGCGGUGGUUUAUGUCUGUAAUCCCAGCACUUUGGGAGGCGGAGGCGGGAGGACUGUUUGAGCUCAGGAGUUUGAGACCAGCCUGGGCAACAUAACAAGACCCUGUCUCUACAAAAAUAUAUAAAUUAGCCGGGUGUACUGGCUCACACCUGUAGCUACUUGGGAGGCUGAGGUGGGAGGAUCGCUUGAGCCUGGGAGGUCAAGGCUGCGGUGACCUGUGAUUGCACCACCAGGAGACCCUGUCUUAAAAAUGUAUAUAUAAAAAUAAAAAGAACAUCAGACAUCACCAUCACCUCGCUUAGAAUCCAUGGGGCCUUCUCCUCAAAUUCAAUCUUCCCAGGCAUUUCAUGAACUUGCGUCUAGUUUCUGUUCCCUCUCAAAUUGCCCAGGCUGUCCUGUGAGUGACAGCAGCUAUUUCGUGGGCCUCCUCUGGAAUCAUGAGAAGUCACCCAAACAAUCUCAGUUUUCUAGCUCACUCCGUCUUGACAUUUCUACACUGUCAUCCUUGGUUUUCUUGGAAAUUAAUUUGCUUUUCUUCAUUGUCUUUCUUUGGAGCUGCUUUCCUUUUGUUGGUUACUAUUUUAUUUUUAGCUUCUCACACCAUACCGACAUAUGUUGGUUAUUCUUUUAGACAUGUUUUUUGUUGUUGUUGUCACCUGGAACUUUUGUAUCUUGAAUAAAUUUGGGGAUCAAAUACA